AGAUGUGUUGGCUGCGGCCCCGACUUCAGCGGUUGGGCUAGGCUGUGCUGACUGUUUGGGUGGCGGACCCCGGGAGUAAAACCUGUUGUCGAUCCCUCAGCUUCCAGCUUGCGGCUUGCUGAGUGGCCACCUUCUUUCCGGUCCCCGGAGCUGCGGGGAAAGAUGGAACGGCACCAGCCGCGGCUGCACCACCCGGCCCAAGGCUCAGCCGCUGGGACUCCCUACCCUUCCUCAGCCUCUCUCCGCGGCUGCCGGGAAAGCAAGAUGCCGCGCAGGAAGGGCCCCCAACACCCUCCGCCGCCCAGUGGCCCCGAGGAGCCUGGGGAGAAGCGCCCCAAGUUUCAUUUAAAUAUUAGGACACUGACGGAUGAUAUGCUGGACAAAUUUGCCAGCAUAAGAAUUCCAGGGAGCAAGAAAGAGAGACCUCCACUUCCCAACCUGAAGACUGCAUUUGCAAGCAGUGAUUGCUCAGCAGCACCUUUAGAGAUGAUGGAGAACUUUCCAAAGCCACUGUCAGAGAAUGAACUCUUAGAACUUUUUGAAAAAAUGAUGGAAGAUAUGAAUUUAAAUGAAGAUAAAAAGGCACCAUUGCGGGAAAAGGACUUCAGUAUCAAAAAAGAAAUGGUGAUGCAGUACAUUAAUACUGCUUCUAAGACAGGAAGUCUUAAGAGAAGCCGACAGAUCUCACCUCAGGAAUUCAUUCAUGAGCUGAAAAUGGGGUCUGCAGAUGAGAGACUUGUCACAUGCCUGGAGUCUCUCCGAGUGUCUUUGACCAGCAAUCCUGUGAGUUGGGUGGAAAGCUUUGGACAUGAAGGGCUUGGAUUAUUAUUAGACAUUUUGGAAAAACUGAUUAGUGGAAAAAUCCAAGAAAAAGUUGUAAAGAAAAAUCAACAUAAAGUCAUACAGUGUCUAAAAGCCCUGAUGAAUACGCAGUAUGGCUUGGAAAGAAUUAUGAGUGAGGAGAGGAGCCUUUCCUUAUUGGCCAAAGCCGUGGAUCCCAGACACCCCAAUAUGAUGACAGAUGUGGUUAAACUUCUCUCUGCGGUAUGCAUUGUAGGGGAAGAAAGCAUCCUUGAAGAAGUUUUAGAAGCUUUAACUUCAGCUGGUGAAGAAAAAAAAAUUGACAGAUUUUUUUGUAUUGUGGAAGGCCUCCGGCACAAUUCAGUUCAACUGCAAGUAGCUUGUAUGCAGCUCAUCAAUGCCCUGGUUACAUCUCCUGAUGAUUUGGAUUUCAGGCUUCACAUCAGAAAUGAAUUUAUGCGUUGUGGAUUGAAAGAGAUAUUGCCAAAUUUAAAAUGCAUUAAGAAUGAUGGCCUGGAUAUCCAACUUAAAGUCUUUGAUGAGCAUAAAGAAGAAGAUUUGUUUGAGUUAUCCCAUCGCCUUGAAGAUAUUAGAGCUGAACUUGAUGAAGCAUAUGAUGUUUACAACAUGGUGUGGAGCACAGUUAAAGAAACUAGAGCAGAGGGAUAUUUUAUUUCUAUUCUUCAGCAUCUUUUGCUGAUUCGAAAUGAUUAUUUUAUAAGGCAACAAUACUUCAAAUUAAUUGAUGAGUGUGUAUCCCAGAUUGUAUUGCAUAGAGAUGGAAUGGAUCCAGACUUCACAUAUCGAAAAAGACUAGAUUUAGAUUUAACCCAGUUUGUAGACAUUUGCAUAGAUCAAGCAAAACUAGAAGAGUUUGAAGAGAAAGCAUCAGAACUUUACAAGAAAUUUGAAAAAGAGUUUACCGACCACCAAGAAACUCAGGCUGAAUUGCAGAAAAAAGAGGCAAAGAUUAAUGAGCUUCAAGCAGAGCUACAAGCUUUUAAGUCUCAGUUUGGUGCCUUGCCAGCUGAUUGUAAUAUUCCUUUGCCUCCCUCUAAAGAAGGUGGAACUGGCCACUCAGCACUUCCUCCUCCGCCUCCACUGCCUUCUGGUGGAGGGGUGCCGCCUCCACCUCCUCCCCCACCACCUCCUCCACUUCCAGGAAUGCGGAUGCCAUUCAGUGGUCCUGUGCCUCCACCACCUCCCCUGGGAUUCCUUGGAGGACAAAAUUCUCCUCCUCUACCAAUCCUGCCAUUUGGGUUGAAACCAAAGAAAGAAUUUAAACCUGAAAUCAGCAUGAGAAGAUUGAAUUGGUUAAAGAUCAGACCUCAUGAAAUGACUGAAAACUGUUUCUGGAUAAAAGUAAAUGAAAAUAAGUAUGAAAACGUGGAUUUGCUUUGUAAACUUGAGAAUACAUUUUGUUGCCAACAAAAAGAGAGAAGAGAAGAGGAAGAUAUUGAAGAGAAGAAAUCGAUUAAGAAAAAAAUUAAAGAACUUAAGUUUUUAGAUUCUAAAAUUGCCCAGAACCUUUCAAUCUUCCUGAGCUCUUUUCGGGUGCCAUAUGAGGAAAUCAGAAUGAUGAUAUUGGAAGUAGAUGAAACACGGUUGGCAGAGUCUAUGAUUCAGAACUUAAUAAAGCAUCUUCCUGAUCAAGAGCAAUUAAAUUCAUUGUCUCAGUUCAAGAGUGAAUAUAGCAACUUAUGUGAACCUGAGCAGUUUGUGGUUGUGAUGAGCAAUGUGAAGAGACUACGGCCACGGCUCAGUGCUAUUCUCUUUAAGCUUCAGUUUGAAGAGCAGGUGAACAACAUCAAACCUGACAUCAUGGCUGUCAGUACUGCCUGCGAAGAGAUAAAGAAGAGCAAAAGCUUUAGCAAGUUGCUGGAACUUGUAUUGCUAAUGGGAAACUACAUGAAUGCUGGCUCCCGGAAUGCUCAAACCUUCGGAUUUAACCUUAGCUCUCUCUGUAAACUAAAGGACACAAAAUCAGCAGAUCAGAAAACAACGCUACUUCAUUUCCUGGUAGAAAUAUGUGAAGAGAAGUACCCUGAUAUACUGAAUUUUGUGGAUGAUUUGGAACCUUUAGACAAAGCUAGUAAAGUCUCUGUAGAAACGCUGGAAAAGAAUUUGAGGCAGAUGGGAAGGCAGCUUCAACAGCUUGAGAAGGAAUUGGAAACCUUUCCCCCUCCUGAGGACUUGCAUGACAAGUUUGUGACAAAGAUGUCCAGAUUUGUUAUCAGUGCAAAAGAACAAUAUGAGACACUUUCGAAGUUACACGAAAACAUGGAAAAGUUAUACCAGAGUAUAAUAGGAUACUAUGCCAUUGAUGUGAAGAAGGUGUCUGUGGAAGACUUUCUUACUGACCUGAAUAACUUCAGAACCACAUUCAUGCAAGCAAUAAAGGAGAAUAUCAAAAAAAGAGAAGCAGAGGAAAAAGAAAAACGUGUCAGAAUAGCUAAAGAAUUAGCAGAGCGAGAAAGACUCGAACGCCAACAAAAGAAAAAGCGUUUAUUAGAAAUGAAGACUGAGGGUGAUGAGACAGGAGUGAUGGAUAAUCUGCUGGAGGCCUUGCAGUCCGGGGCUGCCUUCCGCGACAGAAGAAAAAGGACACCGAUGCCAAAAGAUGUUCGGCAGAGUCUCAGUCCAAUGUCUCAGAGGCCUGUUCUGAAAGUUUGUAACCAUGAAGAAAAGCAAUGUCCAUUCAGACGUGAGGAAUUUGAACAAGAAGGAGAUACACCAUAUACAAAUAGAAACCGAGAUUUGCAACUCAGAAAUGUAUUUAGCACAGAGGAGUAAAGUUUGAAGCCGAAGCCUGUGUUUAAGCCAUGGAGACAGAUGACCUCAAGCUCUCUCCCUCAGGGAAGUGUUCACAUUUAAGGUUGACCAAGGGAGAGUGUGUGUGCGGUUGGAGCAGCAAGGGUGGGUGUCACCAGGGUAAGAGAAGUGAAUGAGCUGCAUACUCAAGUUUGGAAGAAAAAUAAUAGCUCUUUCCACCUAAUUUAAAGAUUAGAAAAUCCAUGUAAGCCUAUCAUUCUAAUUUAGCUCCAACAGUCCAUAGGAGGUCACUGCAUGGACUUUCCCCAGUGGGCUCUGAUUCCAAACUGUUCAAAGUCCUGUAAGGAAGCCCUGGAGAAAAUCCAGCUAUAAAUUAAGAUGGAGUGAAUUACUGAAAUCACUUUCUGAUAAAACCUGGAUUUAAGAUCAUUCUGUGCCCCAAAGUGUUUCUGAAAAGGGUGGGACACAGGGAAAUAAAUUAGUAAGUCAGAUUGGAUGAGAUAACUCUUCUCAAAACCCUCCAGUGAAGUAAGAGACCAAGGGCCAAACCAUCUGUCCCCAUCAUCUCUCUGACCUCAUUUCUGCUACUCCAGCCCUGGCUCACUCCCCUUCAGCUGUCCCAGCCAUCUUGCUAUUCCCAGAACACAUCAGUCUUUGUACUUGCUGCUUCUGUCUGGAACAUCUUCAAAAUAUAUGUAUACUCACUCCAUCUAUUCCUACAGAUCUCUGCUCCAUUAUCCCUUUGUGAGAGAGGCCUACUCCAACCAUUCUUUGUAAAGUAGCAACCACAACCCUCAGCAUGUUGACACUGCCUUUUUCUCCAAUGUACUGACCACCCUAUAACAUAUGUGUUUACCUGUGUGUCUCUUGUGAGCUGCCUCCUGCCUUACUCCUAGAAUAUAAGCUCCAUGAGAGCCAGGGACCUUUUCAACUUUGUUGUCUACUAUUCCUAGAACAGAGCUUGACCCAUAUUAGAAGUUCAGUAUCUGUUGAAUUAAUAAUUGGGUAUUAAAGAUUAUCCUUUGCAAUCACUAAUAUUUUACUCUUAGCAUGUUUUAAUACCAAAAAGGAGAGAGGACAUAAUUUUAAAUUUGUAUAAAUUUAACUUCCCGAAUCAUUAUUUUUCUCAUUUUGCUUCAGUGAACACAUGUAAGCUGCAGUUGGGGACCACUGCACCAUGCCAUCCUAAUUCUUUUAGGUCUGUUAAUCCUUGCCAUCCAGUAUUUGUGUUACUCAUAGGAAAUAGAUUACUUCAAGCUGAUUUAAGGAAAUAAGAAUAUUGCUUACUUCCUAUUUUUUAAGGAAGCAGGAAUAUGGCUUAUUGUGCUAUUCCUUUUGGUAAUACUUUUUCAUGCACUAAUUUAGCAACUUUUUUGCACAUUUGUUCUAAUAUUUAUGCAAGAGAGAUUUUAAAAAGAUAGAUGAAAGGGAUUUUUGCUUAGUUAAGUAUUGUUAAAUAGGAUUUUUAUAUUCAGGUUGCUUCAGCAACUGUUGUGUUUGGUAGCUCUGAUUUUCAAAUGUAGCAGGUUGUCAUGGAAGGUCUGUUGUUACUUCAUUUAUUUUUUUUCUUUUAUUAGUUGUUUGAGGCAGUAAAAUAGGCUUGUGUUACCUCACUAAAAAGACAUCAUUUUAAGUUAUUUUAAGUCCUUGAGAAGAUCAGUUUACCACAAGGAAAAGACUUAAAAUCUCAUAUUAAGCUCAGAGUGAAAUUGUAAUCAGGCAAGCAAUUAUUUAAUUUUCUUCAUGGUGUACUUCAUAAAUGUCAACAUGACUUGUUGAGGGAAAAAUGACAAAAGCAUGAAAUGUAUUGGUAAGUAUGAGGAGAGAGAAGACAGAUCAUUGAAAGGAUGCUGUCCAUAUUUUAGUGGUUGAACAAUAAGCAUUCUUUAGUUUAUGCACAUUUGGGCAUAUGCAUUUUAUUGGACUUUCUUGUUUUCUUUUUACCAAUACAUAACUUUCUUUGACUACCAUAAUUUAAGAUAAUGUAAAAAAAAUGCCAGGAGUGUUAUUUACUUCUGAACAAAAUUGAAUGUAAAAGCAACUAUUAUUUUCAAACAUGAUUAACAUCUUAAAAUGAAAGCAUAAUUAUUCACUGUAUCUAACCCUUUUCUGGGAAAUACAAGACAUUGGCACAAUAAUCAAGUAGCUGAUAAUUAGUUGAAUGAUUUAAAGUUGUUUUUAAACAUCCUGAACAUUUAUCCUUUCCUUUUAUCAAUAGGUAAUCUUUUUCUCAUAGCUUGUGUGGAAGUGAAAACCCAACCUCCCAUCCUCAGAUUCCAGGCUGUUCCAAUGGUGGGCCUCACAGGGAAGAAUGAUUCUUAGAUCUGUCACAUAUCUCUAAUAAUAACUCUGUCAGAGCUAAAGAGGCAGUGCAGUUUCCUGGUAGCUGCGAUGACUUAAUGACCAUCCACAUAGAGUGUAUUUAUUUGUAGUGAUAUUUAAAUAAAUUACAUGAAAUAAUCACAGAUAUUGGUAUAUGAGUUGAAUCCCCUCUUCUUUUUUUUUUUUUUUUUUUUUUUUUUUUUUUUUUGAGACAGUGUCUCGCUCUGUCGCCCAGGCUGGAGUGCAGUGGCGCAAUCUCGGCUCACUGCAAGCUCCGCCUCCCGAGUUCACGCCAUUCCCUUGCCUCAGCCUCCUGAGCAGCUGGCACUACAGGCGCCUGCCACCACGCCCGGCUAAUUUUUUUGUAUUUUUAGUAGAGACGGGGUUUCACCGUGUUAGCGAGGAUGGUCUCGAUCUCCUGAUCUCGUGAUCCGCCCGCCUCGGCCUCCCAAAGUGCUGGGAUUACAGGAGUGAGCCACCGCGCCCGGCCCUGAAUCCCCUCUUCUAAAAACCUUUCUGCUGUCUUACCUAUCCUAUUGUCAGCAUGUGGAGUAGUUUGAGGAGGUAUUAUUCCUAAUAUUUCAGGCUGGAAUUUCUGAAUUUUUACAACUAUCAUUAGGUUAUAAAGCCCUCAACAUACCAUGUGUUAGUCAAGUUCCUACUCAAGUUAAAUGAUUCAGAGGUUUAGAAUAGGAUAAUCCAAAUCUCUUGGGAAUAUGAUUCCCUAAUUCAUUUGAAAUACAAUUAAAAGUUUAUUUUGCAACUAACUAGGAUAGAAUUACAAGUUUACUUUUACUUUCUUUCUGCAAGCAGAAGCAAAUACAUGUCAAUUAAUAAAAUGAGAAGAUGUUUUUGGUUUAUUAAUGAUUUACAUAAAAUCGGGAACCUACUUAACACAUACAAAUAAGAAAAACACCAUAGAAAAUUCAAUUUAGCAUUACAGAAAUUACUGCAAACCAACUCUUUGUCUGUACUAGUAUAUAAAAAUACUUUUAAAAGUGCAUCAAUUUUCACAGCCAUUUAGUAGAUUAGAAAGCAAUUGUAAACAGCAUAAAACCCACAUUAAUGCCUGUCAACAUCCUGCCUUUUGCUCAGUUAUGGAUUUGUUUGAAAUAACAGUGAGAUCUAAAGUGAUUGCAUCAACAUCACAGACUGUAUAAAUAUGAAUGAACCCACCGUAAUGGGAUGCAUAGCACUAUAUAGCAGGCAUUUGUCCUCCCUGUCAUGGUAACAGGUUUGUGAUGUAAGAGAACAUGGCAUUGUCUCCAAGAAAUAACUCCACAUGUUCUUAUACUGUAAUCAUAGCAACUGAUGGGUUUUUAGAUUGCUCUAAAUUUUAUAUUCUAAUAUUGUACUAUUAAAAUCCAUCUGUUGUUUAAUGUUCAAAAAUCAAUCCAGAUAAUAUGAAAUCCAUUGAGCUAUUUCUAAAAAGUGAUUGUUAAUUUCAGUAACAUGCCAUUUUGAUUUUUAGUGGAUUAUCUUGAUGGAUCUCUGCCUAAAAGCAUAAGAUCAACGGAACCAUGUCAUCUGAAUAGAAGCUAGUGAAUGGGAUUGGGUGCAGUAAAAUGGAAAUCCUUUUUAAUGAAAGAUAAGAGCUGCAUCCUUACCUCUCAACCUUUCAAUCCUUUCAUUUGAGGAUUUAGUAAGUUGUUGUUUUCCUUUGUUUGGAAUAUAACGGUGUAUGUUAACUUAGUUCUAGUUCUACUGUUUUAUUUUUAAAGAUGACCACAUUAAGAGGUUUUGGUGGUAGAACAAAUAAUUUUUUAAAGACCUCUUUUAUAUUAUUAAAUUAGAAGAAAGGGUACCAGUGCAUAUCUUUUUAAUUGGUUGACUCAGCUUAAAUUGUCAUUCUUAUUUAGAUAAGGGUCAUUUUAUUCUAGUACUUAAUUUUUUUGUUGGAAUACUCUUAUGCUGGUAAAAGUUUUAGUACUAACUUCUUAAGUACAUGUUUUAGUCUUCAGAAAGGGUAAAGUGUACAUUUCAGUAUUAAAACCAUUAAUCCAGCUUGGUUGUAUAUUGACAUUUCACUUUUUAGCAGAUCAUUUACCUGACUGGAGAUCUCUCUUCUUUGUUAAGAAUGUUGCUUUUACAGUUUUCUGAUACUUAGGAGAGGAGACCAUGGCCAUUUAAUAGAACUAAUAUUUGUCUAGUGACUUUUCUACUGUGCUUUGUGCAUUGUAUUAUCUCAUUUAAUGCAUUCUACCUUUUAUUUCUGUUUGAAGGGAGGAACCAUCUGGAUUGUAACAGCAAGUUCUUUUCAAGCACAAAAGUUCCAGGAGAGAGAGAAUAUAGAUUUAGUAUUAUUCCUCCUGGCAUUCCUCAUUCUAACUUUUGCCAUCACCUGAGUUCCAGCAUUGGGGAAGACAAAAGCACCAGGGUGCACAUCUUUAAAGACAUUUAUGCUGCUUGCCUUCAAGUAAAUAUCAGCUACAACCAGGAAUAUUAGACUGUCUCCCUUUUCCCUGUAAAGUGGGCCUUUAAUGGGAUGGCCACACUUUAUUGAUGGGAAUCCUGUGUUCAAGUUGAGAUCACAGGUACAAAUGAAGCCUAACUAGUAACCUACAAAAUAUAUGCACUAGAAGCUAUGGCAGUGGUUCAAAGUUAGAAAGAUGAUUAGUAUAUUCAUUUUUAUCGACUGUAGCACUUUAUGAUGCUUAUGGAAAUAUUCUUAGUAAAUUAUUCAAUCAAAUAAAUUUUACAUGAGGGUUUUACUAA